AAUUGUGGCUAUAGCCGCCUCGAUCGCUGUCUCCCCAGCCUCGCCGCGGCCGCUCCGGGACGCGCCCGCCCGCCGCCCGGCUCUCCCCCCCUUUGGGCUGCUGCUGCUGCUGCUGUGACUGCUGCUGCGAGAGGAGGAGGAGGAGGAGGAAGCAGCGGGGGGGGGAGCGGGGGGUGGGGGGGGAGACCAAGAAGUACAGUUGGGAGCGAGGGAGCUUCACCCCCGGGGCGGUGGUUGUUUCUUUUUUCUUUCUUUCUUUUUUCUUUUCCUUUUUUUUUUUUUUUCUAAUUCCUGAGGGGUGGUUGCUGCUUUUGCUACAUGACUUGCCAGCGCCCGAGCCUGCGGUCCAACUGCGCUGCUGCCGGAGCGCUCAGUGCCGCCGCUGCCGCCCGCGCCCCCCGCGCCCCGUUCGGCACCCACCGGUCGCCGCCGCCCGCCGCGCCGCUGUCCCGCUCCCGCGCCGCCGCCGCCGUUUCCCCCCGACGACUGGGUGAUGCUGGACAUGGGAGAUAGGAAAGAGGUGAAAAUGAUCCCCAAGUCCUCGUUCAGCAUCAACAGCCUGGUGCCCGAGGCGGUCCAGAACGACAACCACCACGCGAGCCACGGCCACCACAACAGCCACCACCCCCAGCACCACCACCACCACCACCACCAUCACCACCACCCGCCGCCGCCCGCCCCGCAACCGCCGCCGCCGCCGCAGCAGCAGCAGCCGCCGCCGCCGCCGCCCCCGGCACCGCAGCCCCCCCAGACGCGGGGCGCCCCGGCCGCCGACGACGACAAGGGCCCCCAGCAGCUGCUGCUCCCGCCGCCGCCACCGCCACCACCGGCCGCCGCCCUGGACGGGGCUAAAGCGGACGGGCUGGGCGGCAAGGGCGAGCCGGGCGGCGGGCCGGGGGAGCUGGCGCCCGUCGGGCCGGACGAGAAGGAGAAGGGCGCCGGCGCCGGGGGGGAGGAGAAGAAGGGGGCGGGCGAGGGCGGCAAGGACGGGGAGGGGGGCAAGGAGGGCGAGAAGAAGAACGGCAAGUACGAGAAGCCGCCGUUCAGCUACAACGCGCUCAUCAUGAUGGCCAUCCGGCAGAGCCCCGAGAAGCGGCUCACGCUCAACGGCAUCUACGAGUUCAUCAUGAAGAACUUCCCUUACUACCGCGAGAACAAGCAGGGCUGGCAGAACUCCAUCCGCCACAAUCUGUCCCUCAACAAGUGCUUCGUGAAGGUGCCGCGCCACUACGACGACCCGGGCAAGGGCAACUACUGGAUGCUGGACCCGUCGAGCGACGACGUGUUCAUCGGCGGCACCACGGGCAAGCUGCGGCGCCGCUCCACCACCUCGCGGGCCAAGCUGGCCUUCAAGCGCGGUGCGCGCCUCACCUCCACCGGCCUCACCUUCAUGGACCGCGCCGGCUCCCUCUACUGGCCCAUGUCGCCCUUCCUGUCCCUGCACCACCCCCGCGCCAGCAGCACUUUGAGUUACAACGGCACCACGUCGGCCUACCCCAGCCACCCCAUGCCCUACAGCUCCGUGUUGACUCAGAACUCGCUGGGCAACAACCACUCCUUCUCCACCGCCAACGGCCUGAGCGUGGACCGGCUGGUCAACGGGGAGAUCCCGUACGCCACGCACCACCUCACGGCCGCCGCGCUAGCCGCCUCGGUGCCCUGCGGCCUGUCGGUGCCCUGCUCUGGGACCUACUCCCUCAACCCCUGCUCCGUCAACCUGCUCGCGGGCCAGACCAGUUACUUUUUCCCCCACGUCCCGCACCCGUCAAUGACUUCGCAGAGCAGCACGUCCAUGAGCGCCAGGGCCGCGUCCUCCUCCACGUCGCCGCAGGCCCCCUCGACCCUGCCCUGUGAGUCUUUAAGACCCUCUUUGCCAAGUUUUACGACGGGACUGUCUGGGGGACUGUCUGAUUAUUUCACACAUCAAAAUCAGGGGUCUUCUUCCAACCCUUUAAUACAUUAACAUCCCUGGGACCAGACUGUAAGUGAACGUUUUACACACAUUUGCAUUGUAAAUGAUAAUUAAAAAAAUAAGUCCAGGUAUUUUUUAUUAAGCCCCCCCCUCCCAUUUCUGUACGUUUGUUCAGUCUCUAGGGUUGUUUAUUAUUCUAACAAGGUGUGGAGUGUCAGCGAGGUGCAAUGUGGGGAGAAUACAUUGUAGAAUAUAAGGUUUGGAAGUCAAAUUAUAGUAGAAUGUGUAUCUAAAUAGUGACUGCUUUGCCAUUUCAUUCAAACCUGACAAGUCUAUCUCUAAGAGCCGCCAGAUUUCCAUGUGUGCAGUAUUAUAAGUUAUCAUGGAACUAUAUGGUGGACGCAGACCUUGAGAACAACCUAAAUUAUGGGGAGAAUUUUAAAAUGUUAAACUGUAAUUUGUAUUUAAAAAGCAUUCGUAGUAAAGGUGCCCAAGAAAUUAUUUUGGCCAUUUAUUGUUUUGUCCUUUUCUUUAAAGAACUGUUUUUUUUUCUUUUGUUUACUUUUAGACCAAAGAUUGGGUUCUAGAAAAUGCACUUGGUAUACUAAGUAUUAAAACAAACAAAAAGGAAAGUUGUUUCAGUUGGCAACACUGCCCAUUCAAUUGAAUCAGAAGGGGACAAAAUUAACGAUUGCCUUCAGUUUGUGUUGUGUAUAUUUUGAUGUAUGUGGUCACUAACAGGUCACUUUUAUUUUUUCUAAAUGUAGUGAAAUGUUAAUACCUAUUGUACUUAUAGGUAAACCUUGCAAAUAUGUAACCUGUGUUGCGCAAAUGCCGCAUAAAUUUGAGUGAUUGUUAAUGUUGUCUUAAAAUUUCUUGAUUGUGAUACUGUGGUCAUAUGCCCGUGUUUGUCACUUACAAAAAUGUUUACUAUGAACACACAGAAAUAAAAAAUAGGCUAAAUUCAUAUAUAUCUUGAUACUUUUGUCUCUUUUAUUAAGUAGAGCUAAUUUUUUAAAGACCAAUCAACUUAUAGGGAAUUCAAAGGCUUUUUCAGCCAAACUAAAAUUUAAACUGCUCCUUUAAUUUGAACUGACUCUAAAAAUGAAAAUAGUAUUUUUCCCUUUGUGAACAAAUUUUACAAGGAGCAGCCUAUUUAAUAAACACUAGCUUUAAACAAAGUAUAGGCUUUUCAGCUGAUACCUGUAAGUUUCUGUGGAUAUACAGCAAAAAGAGAUAUAAUUUAAUUUUCUGUGCAUAGCUCUUUACCCUGUGUUUAUUUCCAAAUCCAUUAAUAGAAUGCCAUUUAUAUAUUUUGUUUCAGGUAUAUUGUUAAUAGAGCUUGGCAAAUUAUAAAUAAAUAUAUGUAUAUGGUUAGAUAGAAGUGACUAUAAUGCACACAUAUGUAAUAUAUAUAGACACACAGAGCCCUUCAGUUCAGGUACAAUUUGCGCUAUGAAUGCUGCAAACAUUUUUGUUUAAAUAUUUGUAUUUAUACUUUCUAAGUCAGCAUUUAUUUUUGUGGCUGUUUACCCACAAUGAAAGAGUUCUAAUAAAGAUGUGCUGAAGUUGCAAUAUA